AGCGGGAAGACCAUCUCUGCAAGUGCAGCAUAGCCUCGGCCUAGGACAGCGGGAGUGCGUGGCCAAAGCUGUGAGCAGAGGCACAGGUGGUGGCAGACAGUAGAGGCGCCCCAUGGGGAACAUACUGACCUGUCGUGUGCACCCUAGCGUCAGCCUCGAGUUUGACCAGCAGCAGGGGUCGGUGUGUCCCUCUGAAUCUGAGAUCUAUGAGGCAGGAGCUGAGGACAGGAUGGCAGGAGCGCCCAUGGCUGCUGCUGUACAGCCUGCUGAGGUGACUGUUGAAGUUGGUGAGGACCUCCACAUGCACCAGGUUCGUGACCGGGAGAUGCCUGAAGCUUUGGAGUUUAACCUUUCUGCCAAUCCAGAGGCAAGCACAAUAUUCCAGAGGAACUCUCAAACAGAUGCUUUGGAGUUUAACUCUUCUGCCAAUCCAGAGGCAAGCACAAUAUUCCAGAGGAACUCUCAAACAGAUGUUGUAGAAAUAAGAAGAAGCAACUGUACAAACCAUGUAUCUACUGAGCGUUUCAGUCAACAAUACAGCUCGUGUUCGACAAUAUUCCUUGAUGACAGCACAGCCAUCCAGCAUUAUCUUACAAUGACAAUAAUAUCUGUGACCUUGGAGAUACCUCAUCAUAUCACACAAAGAGAUGCAGAUAGAUCUUUGAGCAUACCUGAUGAACAGUUACACUCAUUUGCGGUUUCCACCGUGCACAUUAUGAAGAAAAGAAAUGGAGGUGGGAGUUUAAAUAACUAUUCCUCCUCCAUUCCACCGACUCCCAGCACCAGCCAGGAGGACCCUCAGUUCAGUGUUCCUCCCACUGCCAACACACCCACCCCCGUUUGCAAGCGGUCCAUGCGCUGGUCCAACCUGUUUACAUCUGAGAAAGGGAGUGACCCAGACAAAGAGAGGAAAGCCCCGGAGAAUCAUGCUGACACCAUCGGGAGCGGCAGAGCCAUCCCCAUUAAACAGGGCAUGCUCUUAAAGCGAAGUGGAAAAUGGCUGAAGACAUGGAAAAAGAAAUACGUCACCCUGUGUUCCAAUGGCGUGCUCACCUAUUAUUCAAGCUUAGGUGAUUAUAUGAAGAAUAUUCAUAAAAAAGAGAUUGACCUUCGGACAUCUACCAUCAAAGUCCCAGGAAAGUGGCCAUCCCUAGCCACAUCAGCCUGUGCACCCAUCUCCAGCUCUAAAAGCAAUGGCCUAUCCAAGGACAUGGACACCGGGCUGGGUGACUCCAUAUGCUUCAGCCCCGGUAUCUCCAGCACCACCAGCCCCAAGCUCAACCCGCCCCCCUCUCCUCAUGCCAAUAAAAAGAAACACCUAAAGAAGAAAAGCACCAACAACUUUAUGAUUGUGUCUGCCACUGGCCAAACGUGGCACUUUGAAGCCACGACGUAUGAGGAGCGGGAUGCCUGGGUCCAAGCCAUCCAGAGCCAGAUCCUGGCCAGCCUGCAGUCAUGCAAGAGCAGUAAAAGCAAGUCCCAGCUGACCAGCCAGAGUGAGGCCAUGGCCCUGCAGUCGAUCCAAAACAUGCGUGGGAACGCCCACUGUGUGGACUGUGAGACCCAGAAUCCUAAGUGGGCCAGUUUGAACUUGGGAGUCCUCAUGUGUAUUGAAUGCUCAGGUAUCCACCGCAGUUUUGGCACCCGCCUUUCCCGUGUGCGAUCUCUGGAGCUGGAUGACUGGCCAGUUGAGCUCAGGAAGGUUAUGUCAUCUAUUGGCAAUGAGCUAGCCAACAGCAUCUGGGAAGGGAGCAGCCAGGGGCAGACAAAACCCUCAAUAAAGUCCACGAGGGAAGAGAAGGAAUGGUGGAUCCGUUCCAAAUAUGAGGAGAAGCUCUUUCUGGCCCCACUACCCUGCACUGAGCUGUCCCUGGGCCAGCAGCUGCUGCGGGCCACCACUGAUGAGGACCUGCAGACAGCCAUCCUGCUGCUGGCACAUGGCUCCCGUGAGGAGGUGAACGAGACCUGUGGGGAGGGAGACGGCUGCACGGCACUCCAUCUGGCCUGCCGCAAGGGGAAUGUGGUCCUGGAGCAGCUCCUGACGGGGUGGACGUCAUGGCCCGAGAUGCCCACGGGAACACAGCGCUGACCUACGCCCGGCAGGCCUCCAGCCAGGAGUGCAUCAACGUGCUUCUGCAGUACGGCUGCCCCGACGAGUGCGUGUAGUAUCUGUUUUAUUUGACUGCAGUCUCCUUGGUGCAAAAACAAAAUGGGAAAAAUAAGGAUAACUCAGAAUUUCAAAAGGAAAUCACAAAUUCAGCUAGUAAUAGCAUUUUCAGUACUUUUCGUAAACUAAGUAAAUACACAAAAUGUUGAUUUUUCUGACCAUAAGACAUAUUUUAUGUCCUUUUGCCAAGGUGGAUGUGUUAGUCUCAGGCCCUCCUGGC